CUCUAGCAGCUGCCGCUGAGCCGCCGGACGGACGCUCGUCUUCGCCCGCCAUGGCCGAGAGCGACUGGGACACGGUGACGGUGCUGCGCAAGAAGGGCCCUACGGCCGCCCAGGCCAAAUCCAAGCAGGCUAUCUUAGCGGCACAGAGACGAGGAGAAGAUGUGGAGACUUCCAAGAAAUGGGCUGCUGGCCAGAACAAACAACAUUCUAUUACCAAGAACACGGCCAAGCUGGACCGGGAGACAGAGGAGCUGCACCAUGACAGGGUGACCCUGGAGGUGGGCAAGGUGAUCCAGCAAGGUCGGCAGAGCAAGGGGCUUACGCAGAAGGACCUGGCCACGAAAAUCAAUGAGAAGCCACAGGUGAUCGCGGACUAUGAGAGCGGACGGGCCAUACCCAAUAACCAGGUGCUUGGCAAAAUCGAGCGGGCCAUUGAUGUGGGAACCAGGAGUGCUCGUGUGCUGAGAGCCCAGUGAGGCACGGGAGCGGCGUGGCCCCCCUUCCCUGGGAAGAUGUUGAAGAGGGGCAGCGUUGGGGGGAGGAGGGAGCUGGUGCUGCAGUGGCCAGUGGCUGUGGCUCAUUUCAGGCCUCAAGCUCCGGGGAAAGGACAUUGGAAAGCCCAUCGAGAAGGGGCCUAGGGCGAAAUGAACACAAAGCCUCGAAAUCAGUGCGCUCCAGCUGAUCUCGUUCCGCCGGUUCCCCUUGGCCGCCAGUUCCGUUCUCCUCACGGGCCGAACGGAACAAGGGGUCCAGCUUGCGGGGGACCCUCCCCAGCCCAUUCCUGCUGUCAAACAAACAAAACCUUGCAAAGCG